AGUCCAAUUCCCGCACCUUUGAGGCCCAAGGGGGAGCGAGCCGGUGCUGCUGCAGGCUGAGGCUGCGGCAGAGGCGGCGAGGCGCGGGCGGUGAGGACGGACAGUCACCGACUUAGUCCAGUUCCCUGUGAUCUCAAAACAAUUGUUGCAGCAGGCUCCUGGCAGUCUCAAGCAGUUCAUCUUCUUGGUGUACUGGUUUCCUAUUGUGAUUUUAUCAUGGAAAAUCAAUUGGCUAAAUCAACUGAAGAACGAACAUUUCAGUACCAGGAUUCUCUUCCAUCACUGCCUGUUCCUUCACUUGAAGAAUCAUUAAAAAAAUACCUUGAAUCAGUGAAACCAUUUGCAAAUCAAGAAGAAUAUAAGAAAACUGAAGAAAUAGUUCAAAAAUUUCAAAGUGGGAUUGGAGAAAAAUUGCACCAGAAAUUGCUUGAAAGAGCAAAAGGAAAAAGAAAUUGGCUGGAAGAGUGGUGGCUGAAUGUUGCCUAUCUGGAUGUUCGUAUACCAUCACAAUUGAAUGUCAACUUUGCGGGUCCUGCAGCUCAUUUUGAACACUACUGGCCUCCAAAGGAAGGGACUCAAUUAGAAAGAGGAAGUAUAACUCUUUGGCAUAACUUGAACUACUGGCAGCUAUUAAGAAAAGAAAAAGUGCCUGUUCAUAAAGUUGGAAAUACUCCUCUAGAUAUGAAUCAAUUCCGAAUGCUAUUUUCUACCUGCAAGGUUCCAGGAAUUACUAGAGACUCCAUUAUGAAUUAUUUUAGGACUGAGAGUGAAGGGCGUUCCCCAAACCACAUUGUAGUGCUGUGUCGAGGCCGAGCUUUUGUCUUUGAUGUAAUACAUGAAGGAUGUUUGGUCACCCCGCCAGAGCUUCUCAGACAACUGACAUAUAUCCACAAGAAGUGCCAUAGUGAACCUGAUGGACCUGGGAUUGCAGCAUUAACUAGUGAGGAGCGAACUCGAUGGGCUAAGGCACGAGAAUAUCUGAUUGGUCUUGAUCCAGAGAACUUGGCUUUGUUAGAAAAAAUUCAGAGUAGUUUACUGGUAUAUUCCAUGGAGGAUAGCAGUCCACAUGUAACACCAGAGGAUUAUUCUGAGAUUAUUGCAGCCAUCCUUAUUGGAGAUCCAACAGUACGCUGGGGUGACAAAUCCUAUAACUUGAUUUCCUUUUCUAAUGGAGUAUUUGGCUGUAAUUGUGAUCAUGCUCCUUUUGAUGCAAUGAUUAUGGUGAACAUCAGUUAUUAUGUGGAUGAGAAAAUUUUUCAGAAUGAAGGAAGAUGGAAGGGUUCAGAGAAGGUACGAGAUAUACCACUUCCAGAAGAGCUCAUUUUCAUUGUGGAUGAGAAAGUUUUAAAUGACAUCAACCAAGCUAAAGCCCAGUAUCUCAGGGAGGCAUCUGAUCUACAGAUUGCGGCUUAUGCCUUUACAUCUUUUGGCAAAAAGCUAACCAAGAACAAGAUGCUUCACCCGGAUACGUUUAUUCAGCUUGCACUUCAGCUGGCCUAUUACAGACUUCAUGGACACCCUGGUUGUUGCUAUGAAACAGCUAUGACAAGACAUUUUUAUCAUGGCCGUACAGAGACUAUGCGAUCAUGCACAGUUGAAGCAGUGAGGUGGUGCCAGUCCAUGCAGGAUCCUUCUGUCAAUCUUCGUGAGCGGCAGCAAAAGAUGUUACAAGCUUUUGCAAAGCAUAAUAAAAUGAUGAAAGAUUGUUCAGCUGGAAAAGGAUUUGAUCGUCACCUUUUAGGUCUCUUACUCAUAGCAAAAGAGGAAGGUCUUCCUGUUCCAGAACUCUUUACGGACCCACUUUUUUCCAAAAGCGGAGGAGGUGGAAAUUUUGUUCUCUCAACAAGUCUGGUUGGCUAUUUACGAGUCCAGGGAGUGGUAGUUCCCAUGGUACACAAUGGUUAUGGAUUUUUCUACCAUAUCAGAGAUGACAGAGAACAUCAUGAAAGUCUGGAAGGAUUACACCAUUGAAGAUGCCAUUGUUGUUAAGAAGAAGUCAUGAAAGCAGUCAAGCCCAAAACAAUAAAUUUCUACUAGAGAAAACUAUGUCCAGAUGUACAUGAUUUCACAGGAUUUACGACAGAGCCAGUCUAGGAAAUCAUGAAAGAGAUUGUCGAUAUGGCAAAAAAAAGUGGAGGGUGAAGGAUUUCAAGGUAUGGAUGUUGGGCCAGUUUCAGUGGCUCAUGCCUGUGUUUCCAGCAGUUUGGAAGGCCAAGGUGGGAAGAUUGCUUGAGGCCAGGAGUUUGAGACCAUCCUGAGCAAUAUAGUAAGACCUCAUCUCUAUUAAAAAAUUUGAAAAAUCACGCACUAAUAGUCACCACACCAGAGGAAUUAACAGAAGGUGACUUGAAGGAGAUGAGUGCUUCUGAACCAGAGCCAAAUGACGAGGAGGAAGACAUAGUAGAAGCAGUGCCAGAACUGAUGUUAGAUAAUCUCACAGAAGCGUUCUGAUUAUUCAAGACUGUUUUUGAUGGCUUUUAUGACAUGCACUGGACCCUUCUAUGAUAGGAGCAUUGAAACUAAAGCAAGUGGGGCAAGGGUUGGUACAGUAUAGAAACAUUUUUAGAGAAAUGAAAAAGCAAAAAGAUAGAAAUUACAAUGUAUUUACAUAAAGUUACACUGAGUGUGCCAGCCUCCCCUGCCUCUUCUUUCAUCUCUUCUACCCCAAGACUAGACCACUGCAUUUUAAAUGUAUUACAUGCUGAUUGUAAAAAAAAAAAAGUUGUUAAAUAUAAAAACUACAUAAGAACAAAGUUAUCUACAUUUCCAUUACAUGGCAUAAGACUAUAAUUAUAUGAUGCUCCCAACCUAUAAUGUAUGUAGACUGUAUAUUUACACUGUAAAUAUUUGUGUCCUUUUUUGUGAAUUUCAUUCUUGCUUAUUAUUUCAAGCAGUUUACAAUGCUAUUAAGUAUGCUUUGAGAUAUUUUGAUGGUUGUAUAAUUUCCAGUCUUAGGAUUCCUAUGAUUUAUCUAACUGCUUCUCUACUAUUUUGUUUUUCCAUCAUUACAAAUAAUGUAUAAGGUUAUAAACGUAUCCUUUCUCAUUUCAUCACACCAUUGCCAACUCUAGUUAUUAUAAAAAUUCUGUAGGCUAGGCAUGGUGGCUCACGCCUGUAAUCCCAGCACUUUGGGAGGGAUUACACUAGAUCACUUGAGGCCAGGAGUUCAAGACCAGUCUGGCCAACAUGGUGAAACCCCAUUUCUACUAAAAAUACAAAAAUUAGCUGGUGUGGUAGCACACACCUGUAGUCUGAGUUACUUGGGAACCUGAGGCACGAGAAUUGCUUCACACUGGGAGAUGGAGGUUGCAGUGAGCUGAGAUCAUGCCACUGCACUCCAGUCUGGGCAACAGAGUGAGACUCUUUCUCAAAAAAAAAAAAAGUAUUUACUCAUUUGACAGGCAAAAAAUAACAUAAAUUACUUGUUUACCUAUGAAGUAAAACAUGUUUUCAUUGUUUUUGGCAUUGUGUUUCUUUCAUGAAUUGUCUGUACAUGUAGGAAAGGCUGUUCUUUAGAAAGAUAACUGAAAUUUUUUUAAAAAAUUGACACUUGAAUAAGAAUGGUUAAUCUGUGGAGAGAAACAUGUUUAGAUGCUGCUAAAUAUCUGGGAAUUCCAUGCCAAGUGUAGCUGGAGAAUGAUUCGUGAUCAUGAAUCACGAGGUGAAAACAAGGCAGGACUUCCUAAAGGUUUCUGUAUUACUUUUCUGCAAAUAUAAUCCACUCAGACAUUGGUUUCAUCAUUAUAUACUGGGCUAGAGCAUGUUCUUAUUUUUAUUUCUCUUUGUUUAACUUAAAGCACAUGUUGAAGACAUAAUUUACUCUUUUUUUAAGUGAUGUGAAAAUUGCAUGGUUUUCCAGAAGCAUUACAUUGCACAUUUUAAUUUUGAGCCUAAUUCAUAUUUCGCUAUAGAAACUUCUGUCUGUAAAGUGGAAGACUAGCUCUAAGUCAGGCUUCUCUCCUAUUUAUUUCAGCUUCCCAGGGCCACUUUUCUCACUUGCCAGAUCUGGGAUUUCUUAUUAGGAGUAUCUCGAGAAAGAUGGUGGAAGGCAUGACUUGAUCCCAAGAGUUUCUCUUUUUGACUCCUAGAAAUAGCCUUUCUCACCUAUCAUCCUUCUCUGCCUUUUUUUUUUUUUCAAACUUUCUUCAAGUACUCUUUAAAAACAGUUUAAAUUUCAUUAAAAACUGUAGCAUGAAUUCAUAUUCCAACUCAUUCCAGUAGCACUUUAGGAAGGACUUUUCUAGGAAGGAGGUUUUUUGUUCUGUUUUAAACGCAGUAAGACCUAGCUUCAGAGCACUCUAGGGCUCUAGCUAAUUUGUUCCCCUUUGUCCCUAGGUGCUAGUCAUCUAAUGAAUGAGGUGUUUCUUAGCAUUAUCUACAGAUAUGGCUUUACCUUCAAUUGUGUCAGGUUACAUUUACCUAAUGUCAGCAAGACUUCACAUUUCAUGUAUGAAUAUCCAGAUGAAAUAAAGUCCUGGUUGUAUUCACCAUCA